GUGACGCUCAGCCGGGCCUUGUGGAGUGCGGGUCUCUGCUGCGGACGCCGGGGGCCGGCGCGGCGUUGGCCGCCCCCGGCCUCGCCGAGUGCAGCGCGCCCGAAGGCCAGUGCCUGCGCUCCGUCCGCGGCCCGGCGCCCAGGGUGGGCGGGGAGGCCGCCGCGCAGUCGCCGCACGCUACACCGCCGGCGCCGUCGUUUCGCGUCGCCCGCUUCCGGCCACCGCGGCCGCCAUUUUGUUCGCGCGGAAGCGCCGCGGUAGGGUGGGAACCCAAGCGGGAGAGCCGCGGGAUUUGCGGCCGCCGCCAUGCCGUCGUCCCCGCUGCGGGUGGCGGUGGUGUGCUCGAGCAACCAGAACCGGAGCAUGGAGGCGCACAACAUCCUCAGCAAACGGGGAUUCAGCGUCCGAUCCUUUGGAACAGGGACUCACGUGAAGCUUCCAGGACCAGCUCCCGACAAGCCCAAUGUUUAUGAUUUCAAAACCACAUAUGACCAGAUGUACAAUGAUCUUCUUAGGAAAGACAAAGAACUCUAUACACAGAAUGGGAUUUUACAUAUGCUGGACAGAAAUAAGAGAAUCAAGCCCCGGCCAGAAAGAUUCCAGAACUGCAAAGACCUGUUUGAUCUGAUCCUCACUUGCGAAGAGAGAGUGUAUGACCAGGUGGUGGAAGAUCUGAAUUCCAGAGAACAGGAGACCUGCCAGCCUGUGCACGUGGUCAAUGUGGACAUCCAGGACAACCACGAGGAGGCCACCCUGGGGGCGUUUCUCAUCUGUGAGCUCUGCCAGUGUAUCCAGCACACGGAAGACAUGGAGAACGAGAUCGACGAGCUGCUGCAGGAGUUCGAGGAGAAGAGUGGCCGCACCUUUCUGCACACCGUCUGCUUCUACUGAGCCCAGCGCCCGCAUGGAGCCGCCUCUGGAGCUUCCUGUUGUUCAUACUUUUUCCUUCCUGACAUUUGUUUUUACUUACAGGUGUUCUGCUGGUGACGGUAGCAUUACCCAAAUAAACUGUGCAUAUGAAAUGGGAGAGGAGAUGCCAAAACGCCAGAUGAAAGCAAUCAAGUUUCUUCUUUUCCACUUUUACUUAUGAGCAGGAUAUUGAUUACAAAGUUUUUCUUCUUUAACCAAAAAGGAAAGACAACGGUUUGUGUGCACUUCCCGACAUACCUGUGUCUUCGUGUGCCUGCCUUCCCUCCCUCCUCCCCACCGGGCCGGACUGUACAGAGCCCUGCUGCGGCGUGUUAGGAAUGACCUGGAAUUGUCAAUAAACAGAUGCUGCUGUCA